GGAGUCAGCUGUCCUGGGUUCGAGUCCCAGAGCUGUCGCUAACUUGUGGACCCCCCUCACUUCGUCCCUUGGGCUUCAGCAUAGCCCUUUGCAAAAUGGGGCCAAUAGUAUCAGAUCCAUUGAUGGGUUGGUUGGUUCAUUCAUUCUGGCGCUUUACUAGGUUCUGGUGCUGCAGAUGGAUAGACGAACUUGCCCAUGAGGGGUUCACUAUCUAGUAAGAAAAACAUUUCCACCUGGAUACUCCACAGGCGUGUCAAAUUCAGUAUCUCCUAAACCGCACUACUUUUCUCCACAAACCUACCACUCAAAUCUAAAUGACUGAAAUCACUAUUCAACCAGUCACCCAAGCACAAAAACCUGGCUUGGUUCCUCCUCUCUCACUUACUACAGUCAAUGGACCACCAACUGCUGCCAAUUUCUACUUUCUAAAGCUUUCCAAAUCCAUCCUUUAUCUUGGUUUGUUCUUUUAGGAGCCUACAGAUUAUGGCAAUAACUUCCUAAUGGUUCUCUUUAGCUUUAAUUUUAGCUUCUUCCAGUUCAUUUUUCAUUCUGCUAUAAAGUGGUCUUUUAACAGUUCAAAUAUGAUUAUAUCACUCACCUGCUUAAAGCCCAUUAAAGGUUUUUCAUUGUCUUCAAAAUAAUAGCCAAAGUCCUUAGUGUGGGUUCAAGGUCUUUUCUAAUCCCACCUGGUCUUCAAUCCUUUAUCUCUAAACCACUGUUUCUCAAAGUCUGGUAUAGUGGUGACCUCCAUUGCAACCAACAUGGGAGUACUUGUUAACAAGUGAAGAUGACAGCUUAAUUCCAGAACAAAUGAGACUCUUGCGGGAAGGGGCAGUUCCCAGGAUUCUGUGUUUUUAACAAGUUCUGCACUAAAGGUUGAGAACCCCUGUUCUAGACACUCCAAUUUUUACUCCGCUGUUGAUGAGAUUCAGGACACACUGCCGCAAAAUAUGACUCGUUGGCAUUAGAGGAAACAACUGAAGCAGGAAAGUCACUUUGUGUCUUCCCACUUUUCUCCCCUGAAGCAGGCCAUAAAAGAAUUGUUUGACCUUCUUCUGUAUAAGACCCUUCAGUGAGAGGUGCUCAUCCUGUAAGUAUAGGAUCGAGGAAAGGAAUGCCCUUAUCUUUGAAGACACAGGUACACAGAGAAGAAUCAGAACAAAUAGGCCUUGCUAAAUUCUCCCCAGCGUAUUACUGUUAGAUCAUACCCCCUUUUUCCAGUCUCAGCCAUGAACCUAAUUCUCCCCUCAACUAUCUACGUAUGUUUCUCUCAACACACUUUACUGUCUUUUAUGCCUUUGUACACUCUCAGUUUGGGCUACUGUAAAAAAAAAAUAGCAAAAACUGGGUGGCUUAAACAACAGAAAUUUAAUUCUCACAGUUCCGGAGGCUGGAAGUCCAAAGUUAAGGUGCCAGCAUGGUUGAGUGCAUGGUGAUAGCUCUCUUCCUCGGUUUGUAGAGAUCUGUCUUCUUGCUGUAUCCUCACAAUGCAGAGAGACCAUCUCUGUAGUGUCUAGUCUCAUAAGGACACUAAUCCCUUUCAUGGGAGCCACUCUUAUGACCCAAUUAUCUCCCGAAGGCUCUAUCUCCUAAUACCAUCUCAAUGGGGAUAGGGCUUCCACAUCACCAUUUUUGGGGAACACAGCAUUCAGACAAUAGCAUCCACAAAACUCCUUCGUUACUUUAGUGAUUUCCUCCUCAUUAUUCAAGGCUCAGGGAAGACUUCAUUGACUGUGCACCACCCCCUCAGCCCUAGACCAGGUUAGGUUCAUUCUUGCAGACUCUCACAAAGCCUUGUGCUGACUCCUCGACAUUUAUCCCACUGUACUGCAAUCAUAAUUGUAUAAUUGUGUUAGCAUUGUGGGUUUGACAGUUGUGAGCACUUGAGAGAACGCAUGAGACCCAUUCUUCUCUGCCCUCACCCCCAGCACAGAGCCUACCAUAUAGGUGUUUAUUAAAGGGCUCUUGAAUGAAGGAGUGAUUUAGGGCCAGAUGGAGAGGAGUUCAAGAAUUAGUUGGGCCUUUGGAAUCAUGUGUCAGCCUGACGGUGUAUGGGAUUCACAGGAAGAUGGUCUCCCUGGCACUGGCUUCACUGCUGCUUUUGAUAAGGAUGUUUCUACCCUUGAGAGGAAUUUUAACCAAUGGGAUUUAAAGGGAGUCAUAAAAGAACUGGACUUUUAAGUGGAAACAGUUUUUUUUUUCUUGGUCUAUAUACCUCACUAACAGAUAGUCAUAAAAAAAUUUUGCUUAAAUUUUUGUUUAUCUAGAAAAUAAGUUCAUUUUCAAAAACUUAGAAAGUACAUUGCAAUUUUAAAAAUAAACAUCACCCACCAUUCCACAACCUAGAGGGAUCUACUUUAAAAUUUCGUUUUUGAGCCAGGUGCAGUGGCUCACGUCUGUAAUCCCAGCAAUUUGGAUGGCCAAGGCGGGAGGAUUGCUUGAGGCCAGGAGUUUGAGACCAGCCUGGGCAACAUAGUGAGACCUUGUCUCUAACAAAAAAAGGAAAGAAAAAAAUUAGCCAAGUGUAGUGGUAUGUGCCUGUGGUCCCAGCUACUUGGGAGGCUGAGGCAGGAGAUUUGUUUGGGCCCAGAAGUUAUAGUGAGCUAUGAUUGUGCCACUGGACUCCAUCCUAGGUGACAGAGUGAGACCCUGUCUAAAAAAAAAAAAAAAAAAAUUGUUUUUGUUUAAUUGUAUUGGUUUUCUUUUUAAAUUUAUACUCAUGUUUGAACAUAAUUGGUAUAAUGCCAAUUAUAUAUGGCUUUUUAUCCUGCUAAUUUUACUUAACAUUAUGUUUUGGGUUUUUUCCCCCAUCAGUAAAAAUUUUGGGUAAAAAAAUAUUUAAUUGCUAUUUAACUUAUUCAUUGAACAAAUAUUUCUUAAACAGCUAUUGUGUGCCGGAUCUUACUUUAGGCAUGGGAUACAGCAGUGACCAGAAUUAUGUCCUUACUCUCAUGGAGUUUACAUUCCAGUAGGAUUAGGCUAAUAAAUGAGCAAAUGAAUAUAAGCAUCACCAAAUAAUAAAUGUCAUGAAGAAUAAAGAUAUUCUAUAGUGUCACUCUGUUUUUUAGUAAAGUCUUCCUAAUUUACCUUCUUUAAAGGAGUGUAUGAGUGUCUAUCAUUUUGUUAUGUCAUCAGUGAAUAUGAUCAUUUAAAAAUUUAUUUUGGUCAAUAAUGAUAGUUCUUUGUAAUAUGCAUGUCUGAUUAUUCAGGAAGUUGAACAUUUUUAGAUAGCCAUGUACAUUGCCUCUUCAUUGAGUUUUCUAUCCAUGUUUUCUGUUUCUUUUCCUAUUGAGGACCUGGUAUUUUCUUCUAUUUUGAACUCGCCCUUCAUAUUAUUAUUUUUUGGGACACUUACAUUAUGAUGGAUAGACAAAUGUAUACUCUUAAACAGUGGUACAGUGAGGCUGUAAGGAGUUAGAAAAACCAGAGGAAGCCUGGAAUUCCCUUCCUCUCUUUCUGCCCCUCCCUCUUCCUUCUAUUGCAAUGAAGAAAUAGUGAUCAGAGAGGGAAGAAGUAUAGGUUAGGUGGAAAUACGUGAAGGAAGAAAGAAAGGUGGAUGGAUGUGUGGGUGGAUGAGAAGAUGAAGAUGAUGGAAAUAGAAGGGAGAAGAUGAGCUGAGGCCAGAGGAGAAGUGCAAAUCUCUAGAAGAUGACGGUGUUCUUUAAAACGCUUCGAAAUCACUGGAAGAAAACUACAGCUGGGCUCUGCCUGCUGACCUGGGGAGGCCAUUGGCUCUAUGGAAAACACUGUGAUAACCUCCUAAGGAGAGCAGCCUGUCAAGAAGCUCAGGUGUUUGGCAAUCAACUCAUUCCUCCCAAUGCACAAGUGAAGAAGGCCACUGUUUUUCUCAAUCCUGCAGCUUGCAAAGGAAAAGCCAGGACUCUAUUUGAAAAAAAUGCUGCCCCGAUUUUACAUUUAUCUGGCAUGGAUGUGACUAUUGUUAAGACAGAUUAUGAGGGACAAGCCAAGAAACUCCUGGAACUGAUGGAAAACACGGAUGUGAUCAUUGUUGCAGGAGGAGAUGGGACACUGCAGGAGGUUGUUACUGGUGUUCUUCGACGAACAGAUGAGGCUACCUUCAGUAAGAUUCCCAUUGGAUUUAUCCCACUGGGAGAGACCAGUAGUUUGAGUCAUACCCUCUUUGCCGAAAGUGGAAACAAAGUCCAACAUAUUACUGAUGCCACACUUGCCAUUGUGAAAGGAGAGACAGUUCCACUUGAUGUCUUGCAGAUCAAGGGUGAAAAGGAACAGCCUGUAUUUGCAAUGACCGGCCUUCGAUGGGGAUCUUUCAGAGAUGCUGGCGUCAAAGUUAGCAAGUACUGGUAUCUUGGGCCUCUAAAAAUCAAAGCAGCCCACUUUUUCAGCACUCUUAAGGAGUGGCCUCAGACUCAUCAAGCCUCUAUCUCAUACACGGGACCUACAGAGAGACCUCCCAAUGAACCAGAGGAGACCCCUGUACAAAGGCCUUCUUUGUACAGGAGAAUAUUACGAAGGCUUGCGUCCUACUGGGCACAACCACAGGAUGCCCUUUCCCAAGAGGUGAGCCCGGAGGUCUGGAAAGAUGUGCAGCUGUCCACCAUUGAACUGUCCAUCACAACACGGAAUAAUCAGCUUGACCCGACAAGCAAAGAAGAUUUUCUGAAUAUCUGCAUUGAACCUGACACCAUCAGCAAAGGAGACUUUAUAACUAUAGGAAGUCGAAAGGUGAGAAACCCCAAGCUGCACGUGGAGGGCACGGAGUGUCUCCAAGCCAGCCAGUGCACUUUGCUUAUCCCGGAGGGAGCAGGGGGCUCUUUUAGCAUUGACAGUGAGGAGUAUGAAGCGAUGCCUGUGGAGGUGAAACUGCUCCCCAGGAAGCUGCAGUUCUUCUGUGAUCCUAGGAAGAGAGAACAGAUGCUCACAAGCCCCACCCAGUGAGCAGCAGAAGACAAGCACUCUGAGACCACACUUUAGGCCACCGGUGGGACCAAAAGGGAACAGGUGCCUCAGCCAUCCCAACAGUGUCGUCAGAGGGUCCCCAGGGCAUUUUCAUGGCAAGUACCCCUCUGCCCCCACUCCAGCAGUGCUUCCCAAAGUGUGCUCUGUCACCUGCUUUGCAAUCGGCUUCCAUUAGCGCAUGUUUUAUUUUGGUGUGACGGUUGGCCCUCCUAAACACGGACUUUCCUCAGGCUGGUUCAAGACGGAAAAGGACUUUCUUCUGUUUUCUUCCAAAGUGCAACCACAGUGGAGAGCCCACGGUGGGCUUAGCCUGCCUAGGCCCUUCCAUUUCUCUUCUUUGACCGUGCUAGGAAUUCCAGGAAAGUGCAUUCCUGCCCUGGUGACCUUUUCCUAUGUCUAGGCUCCUCCACAGGUGCUGCUAUUUUGUGAGCUCCGGCUCCUGUUUAGCUUUUAUUUCAGUUCUAACCUCAGUCCAGAAACAUAUGUGAGGUUGUUUCCCUCUUCAGCCACGGCUACAAUACCGGAAAAUGCUAGUUUUUAUUUAUUUUUUUAAGUAGUGCUUCCUAAAUGGUUUGCAUGAGAGCCACCUGGGGUACAUGUUGAAAACUUAUUUGGGGUCUACCCCAAACCUAAUAACCCAAAUUUGGGGAUGGGGCCCAGGAAUAUGCAUUUUUAAAAAGUCAUCUGCCCUUCCCAGGUGAUUCUGUAAGUUGUCCCUCAACUGUACUUGGAGAAAUCGUGUUUUAAAGCAGUAGUCCACAAAGUAUUCUGCUCAUGUGCCCCCAAAAGUAUUUUGAAAAAUCAUGUAUACCCUCACCCAUCUAAGUUGAUAUCUAAAAUUUUAUCUAAGUUGGUAUCUAAAAUUUUUCAUGGGAAGUUAAAUAGUUGACAAAGUAUGUAUUUGCUGGUGUCGUGUAAAUAUUGGUAUUUUAAAAUAAAAACUGUUACAUCACUAUUUUAAACAUAUCCAGUACAAUUUAAAUAUCACAACAAUUUGACACCCUUCAUUCAUUUAUAAAAAUAAAUGAGCUAGUUCUUUAGUAGUUAAACAUUUCAAAUUGGCUUUUCUCCUUCUGUAUUUCCAUACCACUUUUCAGCCAAGAAUCCUAUCAUAAUGUAAUCUAUUAUGCCCGACAUCUUUUAAUCAUUCACCCCAUUACUUCUUGUCAACAAAAAAUAUAAAUGGAAAUUUUUUUUUUAGCUCUUGCUUUAAGUGUUUGUUUGUUAUCUCAGUCCAGAACCAAUAUUAUCGUAAUUAAUUAUUGGUAUAUAAUGAAAACGGUAUUAAUUCUUGGAUGAUUAAAAGUUUUUUUAUUAGAAUGUUCUUUAUCCUAAUUAGUUCAUUUAUCCAAGAAUACAUGAAUGUGAUUUACAGCUGAGAUGGGGUUCAACCUCAGCUGUAUUCCUUGUUUCUGUAUAGAUGUAAGCACAUAAAUUCGAUGGAAUAGAAUUACGUUAACAAUGUUUUUACAGUUCUUUGGAUUCCUUUGGCAUUUUGACAAAGAUCACAGUGCUCUAUCAUCAAGAAUUAUUAAUGAUGAUCUAUCAACUAACAAACAACUUGAUUAGAUUCUCCUUUAGUCUGUUGAAAGCAGAGAACUGAAAUCCACCUGAUUUACCAUGGCUUUGCCAGCCAGUCAUUAGCACCAUUUACUUUUACUAUCGCUGACAUUUUCCUUUGUUCAGUGGCCCUGAGGUUCUUACACUCUAGGGGGCAGUGCACCACAGGAAGAUAGAUCAAUGAGGGAGGAUUGCGAGGGGGAAGGGGAGGAAGCAGAGCUGGCAGGCCUUAGCUACAGGCUCUCUCUCAGGCAGAUCCCUUUUAAGAUACAUACACCAUGCCCACACAUCCCAUGGAGAGAGACCAAUGCUUUAGUAGAUUACAGAACAGCUAUGAAAAGUCCAUGAAUGAAGAUCACAAAAAGGAAGGCUUUCUUAUUUCAUACUGUAUUCUUCAGGGUGGUAAAAUUUCUGCUUUUGGCAAAAACAUAACAGACGGUUCCAAACAUCAGCAUAAAGAUCACUCAUCCCAUACCACCCACAGGUAGGGAGGAAGGAUGCUGUAGUAUAUGAAAACAAAAGUUUUCACCUGAGCUGAGAGCAUUUAGCAUAUCGUGGUUCUGUAACAAUAUCAAGGACCAGUGCAGAAUCUGGCUUUCUUUUCUGAUAGGCUACCAGUGUGUGUUUAUGUGUGCUCAUUUUGUGGUUCUAAUCAUAAUGGUACAUAUAAUUAGGGAAGGAUAUGGAAGCCACUUUAGAAUCUUAUUCAUUUUUAAAUAUAAAUAUGCCUUGUUUCAAA